CCUUUCUCGGAAACGCGGCGCGGCCGGCUGCCGGAAAACAGGGCAGACCUGUAUGGUUCGUUUAUUCCUGGGGUUGUCAUAUCAUGGCUUAUAAUGACACAGACAGAAACCAGACUGAGAAGCUCCUAAAAAGAGUACGAGAACUGGAGCAAGAGGUGCAAAGACUUAAAAAGGAACAGGCCAAAAAUAAGGAGGACUCAAACAUUAGAGAAAAUUCAGCAGGAGCUGGAAAAACUAAGCGUGCAUUUGAUUUCAGUGCUCAUGGCCGAAGACACGUAGCCCUAAGAAUAGCCUAUAUGGGCUGGGGAUACCAGGGCUUUGCUAGUCAGGAAAACACAAAUAAUACCAUUGAAGAGAAACUGUUUGAAGCUCUAACCAAGACUCGACUAGUAGAAAGCAGACAGACAUCCAACUAUCACCGAUGUGGGAGAACAGAUAAAGGAGUUAGUGCCUUUGGACAGGUGAUCUCACUUGACCUUCGCUCUCAGUUUCCAAGGGGCAGGGAUUCCGAGGACUUUAAUGUAAAAGAGGAGGCUAAUGCUGCUGCUGAAGAGAUCCGUUAUACCCACAUUCUCAAUCGGGUACUCCCUCCAGACAUCCGUAUAUUGGCCUGGGCCCCUGUAGAACCAAGCUUCAGUGCUAGGUUCAGCUGCCUUGAGCGGACUUACCGCUAUUUUUUCCCUCGUGCUGAUUUAGAUAUUGUAACCAUGGAUUAUGCAGCUCAGAAGUAUGUUGGCACCCAUGAUUUCAGGAACUUGUGUAAAAUGGAUGUAGCCAACGGUGUGAUUAAUUUUCAGAGGACUAUUCUAUCUGCUCAAGUACAGCUAGUGGGCCAGAGCCCAGGUGAGGGGAGAUGGCAAGAACCUUUCCAGUUAUGUCAGUUUGAAGUGACUGGCCAGGCAUUCCUUUAUCAUCAAGUCCGAUGUAUGAUGGCUAUCCUCUUUCUGAUUGGCCAAGGAAUGGAGAAGCCAGAGAUUAUUGAUGAGCUGCUGAAUAUAGAGAAAAAUCCCCAAAAGCCUCAAUAUAGUAUGGCUGUAGAAUUUCCUCUAGUCUUAUAUGACUGUAAGUUUGAAAAUGUCAAGUGGAUCUAUGACCAGGAGGCUCAGGAGUUCAAUAUUACCCACCUACAACAACUGUGGGCUAAUCAUGCUGUCAAAACUCACAUGUUGUAUAGUAUGCUACAAGGACUGGACACUGUUCCAGUACCCUGUGGAAUAGGACCAAAGAUGGAUGGAAUGACAGAAUGGGGAAAUGUUAAGCCCUCUGUCAUAAAGCAGACCAGUGCCUUUGUAGAAGGAGUGAAGAUGCGCACAUAUAAGCCCCUCAUGGACCGUCCUAAAUGCCAAGGACUGGAAUCCCGGAUCCAGCAUUUUGUACGUAGGGGACGAAUUGAGCACCCACAUUUAUUCCAUGAGGAAGAAACAAAAGCCAAAAGGGACUGUAAUGACACACUAGAGGAAGAGAAUACUAAUUUGGAGACACCAACGAAGAGGGUCUGUGUUGACACAGAAAUUAAAAGCAUCAUUUAACCAUAGACAAUUUGCCAGGAUCUAGGAACCACCUAAUGGUAGGUGGACAGAAAAGGAAAAAAAAAAAAAUUUACUUGCAAGUACUAGGAAUUCAGAUGAUCAGCUCUUAAAAGAAAAAAAAAAGCAAAAAGACUAAAGCCCUAUUAAGGAAGUUAUUGCUUUAAUAAGAAAUUUCAAAUAUUCUCUUAUCCCGGUCCAAAAGGAUUAAGCGAUUAAAGAACGUAAAAUGGAGAUGUAUUUACAUACACCUGGAAACCUGUGCCUUGUAUUCAAAUUCAUUAAAGCCUAAUCCUGCAAGUA